CUGUUUUCCCACCCCUGGAUUUGUUGGAUGACUCCUCCAACAGUGAAGGUAGAAACACAUUCCACAGCCAUGUGAAUUCCAACUUCGGAGAAAGGGCAUUUUAUGGCUUAAGGAUGACGGCCUAGAAGGGAAGGGAGAGACUUACUUUGGAUUAAAUUUACAAUGGGAAAGUGCUUAAGCUGCUGCAAAGAGGACCAGAGCUUCCAACGAUGUUCUCCAGAAGAUCAAGUUAGUACAGACGCCCAGCAUCGUGGAGCCUCUUCUAUUUCACAACCAAGUAUAUCUCUUGGUCAUAAAACAUCUUAUUCCCCUGUAACACAUAAAGUCAAUGCAGCCAAAGCAAGUAGAAGGUUAUUAUCUGUAUCAAGUCCAUCUUUCUCUGAAAGAAGAUAUUCUUUAUUUGUUGGAUUUCAAAAAAGAAAUGCUUCCCCUUACUGGCAACAAAGUAGAGCUAACUUUGAUUCUGAAGAAGACACAGGCUUCACUGAUAUAAAAUCUUCCUCAGACCAUUGUGGUAGCUUUAUUUCCCGCAGAAGACGUUUCUCAUCCCGUAAACUAAGUAUAGUUUCCUAUUACAAGAGUGCCAUUUUUUUUGAUCCUCAAGCAAGUGGCCAGAAUGUGUUUAAUCUAAAUGAAAUCGAAAUCUUUUCUAAAACUUCAAGUAAUACUGAUGCUAAAAAACAUAUAACCAUCUCUGCUCCUGAAUAUAACACUAAAAAUUUUAAGAAUUUUGAAACAAACACUACUUCUCCAGCCUUUGGGAACACUAUUGAUACAGCCUCCUAUCAACAAAGCACAUCAUCCUUCUUUUCUCUUGCAAGUGAUAUUUCCUCUCCCGAUCAACAAAAUGGAAUUGCCAAUGAUAUUCAACAAAGGGGCCAAUUAUGUAAAGAUUUAAAAGAUUUCCUUCAUCCUCGUCCUGAAAGUUACAGCACAGAUCAUUCUCCAAUCAUGAUUCCACAGCAUCCCUCUCAAAGUGGAACUUUCCCAUUCCUCCAUAAAGCUGGAUUUUCUUCAUCUUAUAAAAAUUCUGGUUGCUUUAUCCCACCUCAAAGCGAAUUAACUUCAGGCCUGUUUGAAGAUGAAGACUUUGCUGUCUUGUUUCAAGAUGAAGACAGAUCUUCACCUAUUGAAAUUCCUAAAAUAAGGUAUAUUACAGCUAAUACUGACACAGAAGAACAGAGUUUUCCAGUCCCUAAGGCAUUUAACACACGUGUAGAGGAAUUAAAUUUAGAUGUCCUUCUUCAGAAGGUAGAUCAUUUACGUAUGAGUGAGUCUGGCAAGUCGGAGAGUUUUGAACUACUUCGUGACCACAAAGAAAAGUUUAGAGAUGAAAUAGAGUUUAUGUGGCGAUUUGCUCGUGCUUAUGGAGACAUGUAUGAACUAUCUACAAACACACAAGAAAAGAAACAUUAUGCUAAUAUUGGAAAAACUUUAAGUGAAAGAGCUAUUAAUAGAGCACCCAUGAAUGGACAUUGUCAUCUGUGGUAUGCAGUUUUGUGUGGCUAUGUAUCUGAGUUUGAGGGUUUACAAAACAAAAUCAACUAUGGGCACCUCUUCAAGGAACAUCUAGAUAUAGCAAUCAAACUUUUACCAGAGGAACCCUUUCUAUAUUACCUCAAAGGGAGAUACUGCUAUACUGUCUCAAAACUGAGCUGGAUUGAGAAAAAAAUGGCUGCUACUCUGUUUGGAAAAAUACCAUCUUCAACUGUACAAGAAGCUUUACACAAUUUCCUUAAGGCUGAAGAACUAUGCCCUGGUUAUUCUAAUCCCAAUUACAUGUACUUAGCAAAGUGUUAUACUGAUCUUGAGGAAAACCAGAAUGCUUUGAAGUUCUGUAAUUUGGCUUUAUUGCUUCCUACUGUUACCAAAGAGGAUAAAGAGGCACAGAAAGAGAUGCAAAAAAUAAUGACUUCCUUGAAGAGCUUUCACUCGUGUCCAUGUGAAGAGACCACCAAACAGGCUUUGUGUGAGCAACAAGGCUAUUUCAUCUGGGUGCAGGCAGACUGAGUCCGAAAAGAGAGUCAGCAAAGGAAGGAGCUGUAGUCUGGAAGAUAAAGAGCCUUUGGUACCGCAAGCCCUGUCAUCUGUGAGUGUGGCACAGUGAAGGCCUGGAGAGUCAUGACCUAGGCCCUGUGAAGUCAAGUAUUUUUACCAAGUAAAAAGAUUGGCAAUAAAACAUUUCCACAUAGUA